ACCGCCUCGUGCCGUACUGGCUUCUGGGUGGCCCUUAAUGUCUUGUGCUCUAAGGUGCUGAGGGGAAAGACGCGGGAGGUCUCUGGCCUGACACUAUGAAGGAAGAGAGAAACUACAACUUCGACGGUGUGAGCACCAACCGCCUGAAACAGCAGUUGCUGGAAGAAGUCCGCAAGAAGGAUGCAGUGCAACUCUCAAUAUUUGAACUAAGACACAAGAUUACGGAACUGGAAGCCAAACUCAAUACUGACAAUGAAGGUAGUGAAUGGAAAACCCGUUAUGAGACACAACUUGAAUUAAAUGAUGAACUAGAAAAGCAAAUUGUUUAUCUCAAGGAGAAAGUGGAAAAAAUCCAUGGAAACUCUUCAGAUAGACUAUCUUCUAUUCGUGUCUAUGAACGAAUGCCAGUGGAAUCCUUAAACACAUUACUUAAACAGCUAGAAGAAGAAAAGAAGACUCUUGAAAGUCAAGUGAAAUACUAUGCACUUAAACUGGAACAAGAAUCAAAGGCUUACCAGAAGAUCAACAAUGAACGCCGUACAUACCUAGCUGAAAUGUCUCAGGGUUCUGGUUUACAUCAAGUUUCUAAAAGGCAACAGGUGGAUCAACUGCCUAGGAUGCAAGAGAAUCUAGUGAAAACCCUCCUCUUAAAAGAAGAAUUGGACCCUUUAAAGGUCAGCUGCUUGGAGACAUUGGGUUUCAGUGCUGCAGGUGUGGCUGGACCAGAGAAUAGGACAUGCCUCGGACAAAAAGCACUCUGGCCCGCCUGCUUACAUGGGUCCUCAACCUUGGCUGUGUGUCAGACUCACCUGAAGAGCUAAAAGUAAAAUACUCAGACAUGUGCACCACCCCCAGGAUUGUGAUCUCACAUGUAUUUCUUUAAGCCUCCCCCAGGAAAUUGUACAGAAAAGAUUGGGACCCACUCUGCUGGUUUAGUGUGGCUUCAUCUCUCAAACUGAAUGAAACUUCUUCCAACUCUCCUCGAGCUGACUUCACCUUGGUCUUUUUAUUUUUACUUUUUUACAGUGAGAGAUAAGGAUUUUAUUUUUUCUUCGUUGUUAUUUAUUUCAAUUUUUAUUUUAGAUUCAGAGGUACCUGUGCAGGUUUGCUAUCGUGGUAUAUUGUAUAAUGCUGAGAUUUGGGGCACAAAUAAUCCCAUCACCCAGGGACUGAGCAUAGUAGCCGAAAGUUAUUUGUCAAUGUUUGCUCUCCUUUCUUCCUCCACCCUCUAGUGGUCCCCAGUGUCUAUUGUUGCUGUCUUUAUGUCCAUGAGUACCCAGUGUUUGGCUAUCACUUGUAAGCGAGAACAUGCAGUAUUUGGUUUCCUGCUUCUGUGUUAAUUUGCAUAGGAAAAUGGCCUCCAGCUGCAUCCAUAUUGUUACAAAGGACAUGAUUUCAUUUCUUUUAUGACUGUGUAGUAUUCCAUGGUGUGUAUCAGGAGUCCCCAGCCUCUGGCCGUGGACUGUUACCCAUCCAUGGCCUGUUAGGAAUUGGGCUGCCCAGCAGGAGGUGAGCUGCAGGUGAGCAAGCAUUACCACCUGAACUCCACCUCCUGUCAGAUCAGCAGCAGCAUUAAAUCCUCAUAGGAGCACGAACUCUUGUGAAUUGUGCAUGUGGAGGAUCUAGGUUGCAUACUCCUUAUGAGACUCUAAUGCCAGAUGAGAAUUUAACUAAUGAUUAAUCUGAAACAGUUUCAUCCCAAAACCAUCCCCUCCCCAAAAUACAGUCCGUGGAAAAAUUGUUUUCCAUGAAACCAGCCCUUGGUGUCAAAAGGGUUGGGAACUGCUGGUGUAUAUGUAGCACAUUUUCUUUACUCAGUCCACUGUUGAUGGGCACCUAGGCUGAUUCUGUAUCUUUACUAUUGUGAAUAGUGCUGCGAUGAACAUGCAAGUGCAUCUGUCUUUUUAGUAGAAAGAUUUGUGUUUUUUUGGAUAUAUACCCAGUAAUAAGAUUGCUGGGUCAAAUGGUAGUUUUAAGUUCUUUAAGAAAUCUUCAGACUGCUUUCCACAGUGGCUGAACUAAUUCACAUUCCCACCAACAGUGUCUAAGUGUUCCCUUUUCUCCACAGUCUCACCAGCAUCUGUUGCUUUUUUACUUUUCAAUAAUAGCCAUUCAGACUGGUGUUAGAUGGCAUCUUAUGGUGGUUUUGAUUUGCAUUUCUCUGAUGAUUAGUGAUGUAGAGCAUUUUUUUCAUGUUUGUUGGCCACUUGUAUGUCUUCUUUUGAUAAGUGUCUGUUCGUGUCUUUUGCCCAUUUUUUUUAAUGGGGUUAUUUUUUGCUUGCUGAGUUGUUUCAGUUUCUUACAGUUUCUGGAUAUUAGACCUUUGUCAGAUGCAUAGUUCAUGGAUAUUUUCUCCCAUUCUGUAGGUUUUCUGUUUACUCCAUCGCUAGUUUCUUUUGCUGUGCAUAAGCUCUUUAAUUAGGUCCCAUUUGUCAGUUUUUGUUUUGGUUGCAAUUGCUUUUGCGACUUACUCAUAAAUUCUUUUGCAAGGCCGACAUCCAGAAUGGUGUUUCCAGGGGCCAGGCCUAGUAGUUCAUGCCUGUAAUCCCAACACUUUGGAAGGCCAAGGCAUGAGGAUUGCUUGAGCCCAGGAGUUUGAGACCAGCCUGGGCAACAUAGUGAGACUGCCAUCUCUACAAAAAGUAAAAAAUUAGCCAGGCAUGGUGGUGCAUGCCUAUGGUCUCAGCUGCUUGGGAGGCUGAGGUGGGAGGAUCACUUGAGCCUGGCAAGUCAAGGCUGCAGUGAGCUGUGAUCAUGCCACUACACUUAAGGCUAGGCAACUGAAUGAAACCCUGUCUCAAAAAAAAAAAAAGUGUUUCCUAGGUUUCUUCUAGGAUUCUUAUAGUUUGAGGGCUUACAUUUAAAUCUUUAAUUCAUCUUGAGGUAAUUUUUGCAUAUGGUGAAAGGUAGGGGUCCAGUUUCAUCCUUCUGUAUAUGGCUAGCCAGCUAUUCCAGCACCAUUUGUUGAAUAGGGAGUCCUUUCCUUAUUGCCUAUUUUUGUUGACUGUUGAAGAUCAGAUGGCUGUAGGUAUGUGGCUUUUUUUUCCUGGGUUCUUUAUUCUGUUCCAUUGGUCUCUGUGUCUGUUUUUGUGCCAGUACCAUGCUGUUUUGAUUACUGUAGCUUUACAGUAUAGUUUGAAGUCUGGUAAUGUGUUGCCACUGGCUUUUUCCUUUUUGAUUAAGAUUGCUCUGGCUAUUCGGGCUCCUUUUUACUUCCACAUGAAUUUUAGAAUAGUUUUUCUAGUUCUGUGAAAAAUGAUGUUAGUAGUUUGAUAGGAAUAGCAUUGAAUCUGUAGAUUGCUUUGGGCAGUAUGACUAUUUUAACAAUAUUGAUUCUUCCACCCCAUGAAUAUGGAAUGUUUUACCAUUUGUUUAUGUUGUCUGAUUUCUUUUGGUGGUGUUUUAUAGUUCUCCUUAUAGAGAUCUUUCACCUCCUUGGUUAGAUAUAUUCCUAGGGGUUUUUGUGUAUGUCUUUGUGUAUGUGGCUAUUGUAGAUUGGAUUGCAUUCUCGAUUUGGCUCUUAGCUUGAAUGUUGUUGGUGUAUAGAAAUGUUAUUGAUUUUUUGUACAUUGAUUUUGUAUCCUGAAACUUUACCGAAGUUGUUUAUCAAUUCCAGGACCCUUUUGGCAGAGUCUGUAGGGUUUUCUAUGUAUAGGGUCAUAUUAUCCUUGAAGAGAGAUAGUUUGAAUUCUUUUCAUAUGUAGAUGCCUUUUUUUUUUCUUUCUCUUGUCUGAUUGCUCUGGCUAGCACUUCCAGUACUAUGUUGAAUAGAAAAUAGCUAUUUUGGGGAGAAUUUUCCAACCAAGAUGUCAAAACAAUAAUGAUGAGAGCAUUACAUGCUAAUUCCCAAUAUUUUCCUUUGACUUAUUUAAAUUUAAAUAAUCCAAUUUUUUUACUUAAUGACCUUGUGGAGAUAUUUAUAAAACACCUUUUGAUUUUUGACUGGGGCUGGAUUUUUAAAAAAUUUAUAAAGAGCUAUAUAGUAUUGAUUUCAAAUAAAUUAUUCCUACCUUUUCUUCAUCUGAAUUAGUUUUAGCAUGUAUAGGAGAUUCCAAAGCAGAGUUACCUAUAUCAAUUUUAGUACUAUUAUUUUCAUAUUCUACUGGAUAAGAAAUUACUUAUUUGGAACUAAGAAUUAUUCUUGCAACAGAAGCUUAUCAGUAACACUAUUUGAUUGCUUUUUGCUGUGUGCACAGGUGAGGACCUGUCUAGACUUCUAUACUAUGUACAUUGUAUUAAUUUUGUUCAUAAAUUAGGUAAUUGAGUUAUAGAUACUAAUUUAAUAUUUAAAAAAUUUAGAUUGUUGAUUUUAAAUAUCAGAAUAACCAAACUGUAACAACAGUGCUGGGAUUUUGGUAUUUAAAAAGGGCAGAGUAUACCAGAAUAUUGAAAACUGGUAUUGAAAUCACUACAUAUAAUUGAAUUAUGAAAAAGUACCUUUAAGAUAAUAAAGCACUACAUAAAUAUGAGCUCAUAUCAUAUAUUUGACAGUAGGGCAUUAUUUUUACAGGUUAACAUUCAAUUAAUCUGACUAUGAAUUAGAAAAAUCUUGAAUUUGUAGAGUUCAUUUAACUUUAUUAAAGCAAUUUGCCAACUCAGCUACAGAAAUACAGAAAAUAUUACUAUCUGGAGAACUACCCAGUCGUAAGUUUAUCAUCGUUGAAAUUGCUUAAGCAGAGAUUAGGUGACCAUUCCUCAGGAAUAGUAUACGAAGGAUUCCUGCAGUGGUGGAGGUGUGUAUUUGAUUGCUGUCAGUGUGCCUUCUGAUACUAACAUUCUGUAAUUCCCUGCUCAUUUAUCACACAACAAAACAUGAGACAAAAAUAACUCCAUAAAAUAUAUGUUGAUUAUACCAUAUAGGUUGUAUACAUAUAGACUAUAAAUAUGAGCUUUCAAAAACGUUUUGCCAUUAGCUAAUAACUAACAAAAUCAGUUUUAUUAGGGUGGUUUUGUGUUUAUAUUGCAUGGUGUUCAAUGAGCUUAUAUCUGUAGUUUUCAUCAAAUGUGGAAAAUUUUGGGCCAUUUUUGUAUUAUUUUUCUGCCCUUUCCUGUCCUCCUGGGACUUUAAUUACAGCCUGUUGUAAACCACUUGAUAUUGUUCCUUUUGGUUCUUUUUUUAUAUCUUCUGUCACUGUAUUUAUGUUUUCCUUUAAGUAAUUGGAUAGGCAUAUAAUGACUUUUAGCAUACUUACACAGUAUCUUUUUCAUUUCUCAGUCUGUUUCUGGUGACUGAUUUUUCUCCUGGUUUCGGGUUUCAUUUUCUGCUUCUUGUAAUAUCUACUAAUUUUAUAUUAGAUGCCAGGCAUUGAUGAUUUCACAUUGUUGGUUAUAGAUUUAUUCUUAUAGGCAGUUAAAUUAAUUGCAGUUCAGUUUCUUCUUUUCAAGCCUUUGUUAGGGUAAGUAUAGAGUGAGCUUCACCCCACAGAGAGUUUAACACCAUUUCUAAGGCAUAGCUAUUGUGGGAUCACUAGAAAAUUCUGUGAGUGAUCAGCUGGGACACUCAACACUGGCUAGUUGGACCUCAGAUGCCUCACAGGCCUGUGUGGCACUCUGCUUGACCUCGUAGAGUUUUGCUCUAGGCUUACAUGUCUUAAUAUCCAGCCACCUCUCAAGGGGCUCCUAUGCAGAUUUCUGGAAUUCUGUUUUUACAUAUCUGUUAGCUCUCUGGUACUCUGCUCUGCAACUUCAGCCACUUCAGCCUCCCUGAACUCCAGCCUCUGUCUUCUCAACUACAUGAAACCACCAUGCUUUGUUUGGGAUCCCCUACCCUGCUCUGAGGUCUGUGCCUGCAGGUAGAAAUCUAGAAUGAUGGAUGGGCCUCACUUCAUUCCUCUCAGGGGUCAUAGUCUUAAGGUGCAUGUCAAUAUCUGCAGUUGUUUCAUAUAUUUUUGACUAAUUUUCUGUUUCUUCACAGUAAGAAGCUAAAUCUUUCCCCUGUUACUCUCAAAGCCAGAAGUAAAGGAUAAAGCAUUAAAAUAAAAGCAAAGAAAAUAUUUUAAAAUCUAAUAUAAAAAUCCA